AGUCGGCGACGCCUCAGAGCGGAAGAGGGAAGUGAAUCAGGCGCCGGGUAGUGGGUUGCUGGGCUGGGCUUGCUGAGGUAGAGGCAGCGCCAAGAAGAGGCCUUUGCCGCUGGUCGGGAUUGGGAUGUCGAAGAACACAGUGUCGUCGGCCCGCUUCCGGAAGGUGGACGUGGAUGAAUAUGACGAGAACAAGUUCGUGGACGAAGAAGAUGGGGGCGACGGCCAGGCCGGGCCCGACGAGGGCGAGGUGGACUCCUGCCUGCGGCAUUCCAUCACAGGAAACAUGACAGCUGCCCUACAGGCAGCUCUGAAGAACCCCCCUAUCAACACCAAGAGUCAGGCAGUGAAGGACCGGGCAGGCAGCAUUGUCUUGAAGGUGCUCAUCUCUUUUAAAGCUAAUGAUAUAGAAAAGGCAGUUCAAUCUCUGGACAAGAAUGGUGUGGAUCUCCUAAUGAAGUAUAUUUAUAAAGGAUUUGAGAGCCCGUCUGACAAUAGCAGUGCUAUGUUACUGCAAUGGCAUGAAAAGGCACUUGCUGCUGGAGGAGUAGGGUCCAUUGUUCGUGUCUUGACUGCAAGAAAAACUGUGUAGUCUGGCAGGAAGUGGAUUAUCUGCCUCGGGAGUGGGAAUUGCUGGUACAAAGACCAAAACAACCAAAUGCCACCGCUGCCCUGUGGGUAGCAUCUGUUUCUCUCAGCUUUGCCUUCUUGCUUUUUCAUAUCUGUAAAGAAAAAAAUUACAUAUCAGUUGUCCUUUAAUGAAAAUUGGGAUAAUAUAGAAGAAAUUGUGUUAAAAUAGAAGUGUUUCAUCCUUUCAAAACCAUUUCAGUGAUGUUUAUACCAAUCUGUAUAUAGUAUAAUUUACAUUCAAGUUUAAUUGUGCAACUUUUAACCCCUGUUGGCUGGUUUUUUGUUCUGUUUUGUUUUGUAUUAUUUUUAACUAAUACUGAGAGAUUUGGUCAGAAUUUGAGGCCAGUUUCCUAGCUCAUUGCUAGUCAGGAAAUGAUAUUUAUAAAAAAUAUGAGAGACUGGCAGCUAUUAACAUUGCAAAACUGGACCAUAUUUCCCUUAUUUAAUAAGCAAAAUAUGUUUUUGGAAUAAGUGGUGGGUGAAUACCACUGCUAAGUUAUAGCUUUGUUUUUGCUUGCCUCCUGAUUAUCUGUACUGUGGGUUUAAGUAUGCUACUUUCUCUCAGCAUCCAAUAAUCAUGGCCCCUCAAUUUAUUUGUGGUCACCCAGGGUUCAGAGCAAGAAGUCUUGCUUUAUACAAAUGUAUCCAUAAAAUAUCAGAGCUUGUUGGGCAUGAACAUCAAACUUUUGUUCCACUAAUAUGGCUCUGUUUGGAAAAAACUGCAAAUCAGAAAGAAUGAUUUGCAGAAAGAAAGAAAAACUAUGGUGUAAUUUAAACUCUGGGCAGCCUCUGAAUGAAAUGCUACUUUCUUUAGAAAUAUAAUAGCUGCCUUAGACAUUAUGAGGUAUACAACUAGUAUUUAAGAUACCAUUUAAUAUGCCCCGUAAAUGUCUUCAGUGUUCUUCAGGGUAGUUGGGAUCUCAAAAGAUUUGGUUCAGAUCCAAACAAAUACACAUUCUGUGUUUUAGCUCAGUGUUUUCUAAAAAAAGAAACUGCCACACAGCAAAAAAUUGUUUACUUUGUUGGACAAACCAAAUCAGUUCUCAAAAAAUGACCGGUGCUUAUAAAAAGUUAUAAAUAUCGAGUAGCUCUAAAACAAACCACCUGACCAAGAGGGAAGUGAGCUUGUGCUUAGUAUUUACAUUGGAUGCCAGUUUUGUAAUCACUGACUUAUGUGCAAACUGGUGCAGAAAUUCUAUAAACUCUUUGCUGUUUUUGAUACCUGCUUUUUGUUUCAUUUUGUUUUGUUUUGUAAAAAUGAUAAAACUUCAGAAAAUAAAAUGUCAGUGUUGAAUAAUUUAUUUUUCUCUGACUUUAACAAUUAUGAAUGUAUGGUUAAUUAAGAGGAAAGGUUUUCUGCUUCUACCACCAAGUACUGUACUCUUAACAAGAACAGUUUGGUAGGGUUUUUAUAAGACUAUAUAGAUAUAAGAUGAUAGAGAAGAGAGUCAUGAAUGAUGUCAGAGCACUACUGAAGCCUUUGGAGUGAUUCCAUAGCCUUCUGGAUGGCAGCUGAAUACCUAUAUGUAGUAUCACUGCCCAAAGACCUAGACUAGAAAGUGCAAAGUAGCUUAGCAGCUGCAGUCAUUCACUCCCAGCCUCCAAAAUUCUCUUUCUUUCACCUCAAAUCUAUUUCUUGUACUUACCUACUCACAGCGACUUCUGUUUGCUUUCGAUCUUCACCUGACUAGAUUCCCACUUUAAAACACUUCCAGGCAAUUCAGGGUCCUAUGGGUGAAGAUAAGCUAAGCAAUAGGUAUUAUUCUUAAAUAUUACUUAGAGAUGGGGACUUGCUAUGCUGCCCAGGCUGGAGUGCAGUGGCUGUUCACAGGUGUGAUCAUAGUGCACUGAGGCCUCAAACUCCUGGCUUCAAGCAGUCCUGCCUCAGCCUCCCGAAAAGGUGGAACUACAGGCACAUGCCACUGUGCCUUAGCCAAUAGGUAUUAGAGGUAGUCAAGUAGGUAUAGCAUAACCAAUUACAAACUUUAAAAUCAAAUGAUACUGAAUGCUUUUUCAUAAAAUCCUUCUUAACAUCACUUUCAUAACUGAAGCGUUUGGAAAAAUUCUGGAGUUCAUAUUUGUUCACAAGAAUGGGUGGGUGUAUUUAGAAUCUGCCAGUCUAUCAGCUUUACUGAGGGGAGAUACUAAAAAUAUUUAACAAGUAGUAUAAUAUAGAGACCGAGUCAAAAUGGAUACUAGCUGGAAACAACUGGUUCAACUGUUGCCUCCUGACUAAAUGUCAGCCCAGGGUAUAGUAACCAUGACACAGUACUAUCCUUGGUGAAGAGUUGGGAAUAGGAUUAAUUGCGGAAAAAAUAUAUAUAAAUGCCAUAGGACACUUUUAGCACAAAAGUAGUUGUUUACCUCCCAUUCUCCUCCUUUAAUCUCAGUGCUUUUACUAUUUGGUUUCUUUUUUGGCAUUUUACAAAAGGGAAGAAAUGGAAAACAUACCCCUUCUUGGUCAUUGGGUAACAGCACCAUUUCGGUAACAGUCAUACUUGAUGACAAGUAUGAUGAUAUUUUAAGGACAUGAACAUGGGUGAAAUCAAUGUGUAGAUGGUACAAAUUAACCGAAUUCUUUUUAAAGCAUUUCCUGUGGAUCCCAGGAUCAUGAGGACAUAACAGAAGAAUAAGGUCUGAAUCUUGUUCACCAGUUUGCUCUCAGCCUAAUUGGGAAGUAAGGUUAAGCACCUGAAAAUUAUGUCAUACAAAAAAAAAGAGAAUUAACGUCAUACAAUUUAGCAUUUGACUGUAAAUGCAGUUAGUCAAUGUUGGGAGAACAACAAAAUCAGGGUGGAUCAGAGUAUUUAAAGUGAGACAUUAAUUUGAACUAAUCCUUUGGAGGGGCAGAAAGGACAAACGGUCCAAGUGAAAUGAACAGAGUAGAAAGAGAAAGUUAAAAGUGGGUUUAAUAGUCACUGUUCUUGCAGUUUUAAUGUUUUUUGUUUUGUUUUGUUUUGUUUUGUUUUGUUUUGUUUUUUUUGAGACAGAGUCUCGCUCUGUGGCCCAGGCGGGAGUGCAGUGGCGCGAUCUCGGCUCACUGCAAGCUCUGCCUCCUGGGUUCACGCCAUUCUCCUGCCUCAGCCUCCCAAGUAGCUGGGACUACAGGCGCCCGCCACCACGCCCGGCUAAUUUUUUGUAUUUUUAGUAGAGACGGGGUUUCAUUCACCGUGUUAGCCAGGAUGGUCUCGAUCUCCUGACCUCGUGAUCCGCCCACCUCGGCCUCCCAAAGUGCUGGGAUUACAUGCGUGAGCCACCGCGCCCAGCUGCAGUUUUAAUGUUUUUAACAUAAGAAUUCUAGAUGGUGCAAAUUAUUAACAGGAUCAGAAACUAUCUCCGUGAUAGAUUCAAGAAAGUAAAAUUAUAGGAAAUCAUAAUGUUUUAUUAGCUGAAAUAGACAUUGAUGAUCACUUAGUUUAACCCCAUGUAUAAAGGUAAAAAAGAAAAUUAAUUAAUUAAUUUUUUUUUUUUGAGAUGGAGUCUUGCUCUGUUGCUCAGGCUGGAGUGCAAUGGCACAAUCUCGGCUCACUGCAGCCUCCACCUCCCAGGCUCAAGCGAUUCUCCUGCCUCAGCCUCCUGAGUAGCUCGGAUUACAGGCACGCAUCACCGUGCCCAGCUAAUUUUUGUAUUUUUAGGAGAGAUGGGGUUUCACCAUGUUGCCCAGGCUGGUCUUGAACUCCUGACCUCAGGUGAUCCACCCUCCUCCGCCUCCCAAAGCACUGGGAUUACAGGCGUGACCACCGCGCCCAGCCAGAUUGAUUAAUUUUUAGAUACACAAUUUUUCCUUUAGAUUUACAACUAACAUCCCCUUACAGACAAAAUAUGUUAAAAGCACCAAAAUAAUUGAAAAACACACCCAAUUAAGGAACAGACCAACGGCCUCUGUAGAACCAAGUGCCCUUAAACAAGGCUGCUUCUGUCCAUAUUCCUGCCGCGGGACCUCUGCCCCACUCCCUCUCCCCCUCACCCCAAUGUCACUAGUACAAUAUGUGAAAACCCCAAUGUGAAAACGUUCUGUGCAGGUGCCUCUUGUAUGAUUCCAGAUAUGGAGGAGGCCCGGGAAGCCCACAGAGGUACAGCAUGUCAUCUGCCUCAAGGUGGUGCUACUUCACCACAUUGAUGAUCCAACCACAAGCAACAUGGGACACAGCAUUCACUUUAACAUUUCUAUUUUCCUUUAUCAUUUCUGUUACUUGAGUGUGUAAGAGUAAUCAACAUAAAUAAUCUAUGUUUACAUCUCUUAUUUCUCUCUGAAACAGUUCCCUAGAAUCCACACCACAUGAAACACAAAUUGAGUAGUGUAUGACCCACCUGAAUUCCAAAGCAUUCUAAAACUCCCGUAUUUUCCAGCCUAGCAGUUAGCUCCUGCUCUGCAAGACACACCCUCUUGACCUUGCUGCUAGACUGUAUGGGCCCCCUGAAGUCAUAGUAGCUGGCUCUUACUCAUCCCCACAUUCACUUGGCAUAGUUGAUGUUCAACAAAUAUCUCUUGGUUGCAUAACAUUGAACGAGCCAAGUCACCUAAGAAAUCCUUAAUUUAUACACAGGUUCUUAGGGUACCUGAAUAGGGCAACACAUCAGAAGUACAAAUUGAGAACUAUACAAAGAGUAAAAUAAUUCUUGGGUUCAAAUACCCUAGAGCCAAUCAAGUUUAGUCACAAAGAAUUUCAAUUCACUUCAAUGUGGACAGUUAAGAAGGGAAUUUAUCAGCCUUAGGUGGAAAUCAGAGCCACCAUGAGUACCACGUGCAGCCCCUAUAGUGUUUAGCUUUGCCAGAAGUCACCAGAGAAAGUGGCUGAGGAACAGAAUUCCAGCUCAUAUCUGGCUAACAGUGGCACUAUGGGAGUUUAUAUGAUCUGUUCAUUAUUCUGUGGCAUCACCUUCUAAGAGCAGAGAUGUGACCCAAUACCCCUUGUUUUCCUUAAAGAUAACCAUUAAAUUAUAUCCAUGAAUUUAUAUCACCGUCCUUGACUUUAUACGUAGAUUUUUCUAAUUCUGUCAACCCUUAGGGUAAUGAAUAACUUAAAUGGCCAAUGCCUCUGAAUAACAUCAUACUUCCUUUUGUUUCUCCAAAAAUUGAAUCAAGAUGCCAGGGCAACUAAGAUUUUCUUCAAUUUGCUAAGUUAAAGGUCAGUGUAUUCAUUAGCCAAUGGUUCUGUAUUUUAUUCAUUUUAGUUUUUAUUCGUUUUCAAAUAAUUUGUUCAUAUUGUUCAAUAUUCAAAAGGUAAGAAAUAUGUACUGUGGUAAUUUUCCAUUCCACCCUAGUUCCUCUUUUGACAACCAACUAUUGUCACUUAAUUCUUAGGCAUCCUUCCAGAUACAGUGUAUGCAUUUACAGGCAAAUACCUAUAUAAGAUUUUACCCCUUUGUGUACAUAAAUACUAACAUACUAUAUAUAGUGUUCUGUUCCUUGCUUUUUUCAUUAACAGUAUAUUUUGGUGGUAAUUUCCUAUCAAUACAUAAAGAACUUCCUUAUUCCCUUCAGAGGCAUUUGAACCAGAGCAAUUCCUUCUUGAAUAGAAGCUGGGUAAAAUAAGGCUGAGACCUACUGGGCUGCAUUCCCAGAUGGUUAAGGCAUUCUAAGUCACAGGAUGAGAUAGGAGGUCAACACAAGAUACCGGUCAUAAAGACCUUGCUGAUAAAACAGUUUGCAGUAAAGAAGCUGGCCAAAACCCACCAAAUCCAAGAUGGCAAUGAAAGUGACCUCUGCCUCUGGCCAUCCUCACCGCUACGCUCCCACCGGCACCAUGACAGUUUACAAAUGCCAUGGCAACAUCAGGAAGUUAUCCUAUAUGGUCUAAAAAGGGGAGGCAUGAAUAAUACACCCCUUGUUUAGCAUAUCAUCAAGAAAUAACCGUUAAAAUGGGCAACCAGCAGCCCUCGGGGCUGCUCUGCCUAUGGAGUAGCCAUUCUUUAUUCCUUUACUUUCUUAAUAAACUUGCUUUAACUUUACAGACUGGCCUUGAAUUCUUUCUUGUGUGAGAUCCAAGAACGCUCACUUGGGGUCUGGAUUGGGACCACUUUCCGAUAACAAUUUUAUUUUUAUGACUGCAUAAUAAUUCUAUUAUAUAAAUAAAUGUACCAUAAUUUACUUAACCAUUUCCCUAUUGAUUUAGGUGGUUUCUGAUCUUUUGCAGUUACAAACAGUGCUACAGUGAAUAGCAUUAUACACAAGUCAUUUUACAUAUGUUCAAGCCUAUUUGUAGAUCAAUUCCUAAAAGUGAAAGUUAAGGUCAGUUGGAGGGCAUUUAAGGGAGAUAUUGCUAAAUUGCCUUUCUUAAAGGUUUUAUCAAUUAUACUUUCUCCAGCCGUGUAGAAGAAUGCAUGUUUUCCCACCCCUUUACCUAUUCUAUGUGUUUGUCAUAAAACAUUUUUUAAUCUUUUCAAAUCUGAUGUUUUAAAAAUGGUAUCAUAUAUUUGCAUUUCUCUUAAUGUAAAUGAGAUUGCACAUCUUUUCACAUGCCUAAUAGCCAGUUGUAUUUUCUUUUCUAUAUUUUUGUAUUUCUAUAUUUUCUUUGCCCUUUUGAUGGUCUUUUUCUUACUGAUUUGUAGGAGCUCUUUUCAACAGGAAUGUCAAAUAUUUCUUGCAUUUUGAGUUUCGCUUUAUAAUAGCUUUUACUAUAAAUAAAAAGGUUAUUUUUAUUUUUA